CAGGGACAGUGAAUAGAUAAGGAUCUGAAGAUUCUGCUUUGGUACUUGUUGGUGGGUUUGCCUUCUGUAGUUAUCCUCACUGAUAAUUGGAGAUACUUAUCAAGUGAUAACUCAAUGCUCAGAUUCACUAUUACAAGUCAUUGGCCAUUCUUCAAAAGUGCCAACCUGAAGUUCUGUCAAAAUGAGCUUGUCAUUACAUCUGCUGUCAAGAAUUCCAGACUUGAACUCACAGCUAUGGGAUUACGACUUCAUACUCGAUAUACCAGGUCCAUAAAAACAAUAUAAGUUUCAACUACUGAAAUGAAAAGACAAAAUCAAAGCUGUGUGGUUGAAUUCAUCCUCCUGGGCUUUUCUAACUUUCCUGAGCUCCAGGUGCAGCUCUUUGGGGUUUUCCUAGUUAUUUAUGUGGUGACCCUGAUGGGAAAUGCCAUCAUUACAGUCAUCAUCUCCUUAAACCAGAGCCUCCACGUUCCCAUGUACCUGUUCCUCCUGAACCUAUCUGUGGUGGAGGUGAGUUUCAGUGCAGUCAUUACGCCUGAAAUGCUGGUGGUGCUCUCUACUGAGAAAACUAUGAUUUCUUUUGUGGGCUGUUUUGCACAGAUGUAUUUCAUCCUUCUUUUUGGUGGGACUGAAUGUUUUCUCCUGGGAGCGAUGGCUUAUGACCGAUUUGCUGCAAUUUGCCAUCCUCUGAACUACCCAGUGAUUAUGAACAGAGGGGUUUUUAUGAAAUUAGUAAUAUUCUCAUGGAUCUCAGGGAUCAUGGUGGCUACUGUGCAGACCACUUGGGUAUUUAGUUUUCCAUUUUGUGGCCCCAAUGAAAUUAAUCAUCUCUUCUGUGAGACUCCCCCGGUACUAGAGCUUGUGUGUGCAGACACCUUCUUAUUUGAAAUCUAUGCCUUCACAGGCACCAUUUUGAUUGUUAUGGUUCCUUUCUUGUUGAUCCUCUUGUCUUACAUUCGAGUUCUGUUUGCCAUCCUGAAGAUGCCAUCAACUACUGGGAGACAAAAGGCCUUUUCCACCUGUGCCUCUCACCUCACAUCUGUGACCCUGUUCUAUGGCACAGCCAAUAUGACUUAUUUACAACCCAAAUCUGGCUACUCACCCGAAACCAAGAAACUGAUCUCAUUGGCUUACACGUUGCUUACCCCUCUGCUCAAUCCGCUCAUCUAUAGCUUACGAAACAGUGAGAUGAAGAGGACUUUGAUAAAACUAUGGCGAAGAAAAGUGAUUUUACACACAUUCUGAUUGUGUUGAGAAGCUGAGUAAGAUUUGGCCACUGCCUGAGUGAACUCUAUUUAAAUUUAAUAAAGGGUGAAAACAGACUGCAUUUUUUGUAUGACUAUGUAAGUUUGUUGAGUUUUUUUAUUGGAAAACGUAUCUCAAUAAAGAACUGCUGUCACUUGUUUUUAGUAGAUACAUAUGUUCUCAUAACAUGACACAACAGUUUAUUCAUCCAUUUCUCUAUUAUGAACAUCCAAGUAGCUACUGGAUUACUGUCAUUUUUUUUUUUUUUUUUUUUGAGAUGGAGUUUCGCUCCAGCCCAGGCUGGAGUGCAAUGGCACGAUCUGGGCUCACUGCAACCUCCACCUCCUGGGUUCUAGCAAUUCUCCUGCCUCAGCCUCCCGAGUAGUUGGGAUUACAGGCAUGCGCCACCACACCCAGCUAAUUUUUGUAUUUUUAGUAGAGACGGGGUUUCACCAUGCUGGUCAGGCUGGUCUCAAACUCCCAACCUUAGAUGAUCCGCCCACCUCGGCCUCCCAAAGCGCUGUGAUUACAGGUGUGAGCCACCACGCCUGGCCUGGAUUACUGUCAUUAAGACAGUGCUUCAAUAAAUGCCUUGUUCCAUAUGCUCAUAUGUACUGAUGUCAUUAUACCUGUGUGAUAGAUUUGCUACAGUGCGGCUGAUAGGAUGAGGAGUAUCUGUGUUUACAAAUUUUAUUAGCUAUUGCAGAAUUACUUUUCAAAAUGAUUAUAGUUCUUCAGACUGGCCUGAAGGCUCACUGUGCUUUGGUAACAGGGUAGAGCUUCAAGAGACCAACAAAUAAGGUGAUGAUGUUUCUAUUUUUGGAUUGAAAAUUUGUUCCACGGAUGAGUAAAAAAAAAGUGCAUCUAUUUUGGGGGGCCAAAAAUGGUUCUACUUCAUGACCUUACACAAAUUAUAAUCCCAAACUGGAUUUCUCUUGGUAUCUUUCCAAAUAUUUAUCCAAUGUUGGUGACCAGAGAGCUACAUGGGAAGUUUCUCAAAUUCUCAUUUGAUAAUAUCAGUAUCUUUUUCAUUUACAGACCACUGAUUUAGAAACUUUUAUGAAGUUUCCUUUUGUAGUCUGUGACAGGAAAGUAAAAUCUUGGAACCCCAAACUCACUAUGCCAAAAGAAAAGUUAAGCUUGGAAACUGGCUCAGGCAAAAAAAUUGCCUUUCCUUUUGUUCCUAAAUAGAUAGCUACAAGAUAUCCGGUCACCUAUCUUCCCAGGUUACCUCCCUCAAUUGUUCUUAAAAAUAAUUGGAAUAAAACUGAUACUGUGAUGUUAAGAUUAGAUAUACAUAUUCUGCUAAAUGAAGGGGUGUCAUUAUAAUUUGUGUAUAUUAUUUGGGAAUAGGCAAUACAUAUAUAUAUCUGUGUGUCUAUUUAAACUGGUUUUAGGUUUAUAA